ACCAGUCUGAGUGUGGAAGAGACGGCGCUGGAACCCAUGGACACGGCGUAUCCCCGCGAGGACACCCGGGCCCCCACGCCCAGCAAGGCCGGUGCCCACACAGCCCUCACACUGGGGGCCCCGCACCCCCCGCCUCGAGACCACUUGAUCUGGUCGGUGUUCAGCACCCUCUACCUGAAUCUGUGUUGCCUCGGCUUCCUGGCGCUGGCCUACUCCAUCAAGGCCCGAGAUCAGAAGGUGGUUGGUGACCUGGAAGCGGCCCGGCGUUUUGGCUCCAAAGCCAAGUGCUACAACAUCCUGGCCGCGAUGUGGACGCUGGUGCCGCCACUGCUGCUCCUGGGGCUGGUGGUGACUGGUGCCCUGCACCUGGCCCGGCUGGCCAAGGACUCUGCCGCCUUCUUCAGCACCAAGUUUGAUGACGCGGACUAUGACUGACAGGCUGGGUCCUGAUCUGGGGCACUAGCCCCAGGACACUGACCCCAGGCUGCUGCCCCUGGGGCCCAAUACUGACUCCCCGGAGCCUGGCCCUCCUUCUGUGGGGCCUCCAUCCCUGCCCCAUCCUGAUCCUGGGGCCCUCCAGCCCCAACAUGGGCACCUAAGGCUGAACCAGUCAGACCCCGGGGUCUUCACCCUAACCCGAGAGUUCCCGGGCCCUAACUCUGCCCCCGAUCCUGCCCCUCCCUCCUCACACUCCAGGCCCCUCGGUUCCACGAUUAAAAGUGCCUGGUUCCAGAAA